AAAAAAAAAAAAAAAAAAAAAAGAAAUGAGUAGGGGCCUUUGGCCCAAGUGUCAAGACAAGAAGUUGGGCCCAGGUGACAAUUUCAUAUGUCUGGUAUUUGAAGCCUCAUCCAUUUUAUUUCCAUUUUCAAGUAUAGUUUUUUAUAAAUUAAAAUGGCAGCUGUGUUUAUUCUUUCCUUCUGGUGUGUAUGCUGUAAGACUAUGAAAGCCCCAAGCAAAGGUCACAGUCUUUCCAGUGCCAGGUUUCUAGAUGAGGGCUCUUGCACAGAGAAUAGGUGACUGGAUGCUGGGCUUCCAGGCCCUGAUCUGCUGCUGCCCACUUGGACCAACAAUGGUUGCAUAAAAUGUUGCCCUCGGGUAAGUAUUUCUGAACUCUGCGGAAGGUUGACCACUGGGGAAUGAGUGUCACUGGCUGGGGUUCAUGGGCUUAAUUCUCAGGAGGUCAGCGUCCUGUUGUCUGUCCUCUCAUGGCCCUGGGAGACAGAGAAGCAACGUCUGCUCUGAUUGGCCUGGACUCAAGGUGGAGUAAACCCGAGAGAGCAAAGACCAUGAAGGGGAUGUUACUCUCCUCCUCUAUCAAGGCCUCGCCCAUCAGAAACUGCCCCCACACCCAGGACCACGUGACCCCGUGCUUCCCCUGGCUCUUCUUCCUAGAGGCCACAUGCCUAGAGAGCUUUGGUGUUGGUGGGAGGGUGGAACAGCAGCUUGCUGGCAGCUCAGACUCAGAGGGUGUUAGCCUGGGGAAGGAAGAAAGCUCAGAGCAUGGAUACGGGAGCUUGAGUCUGUCUGGGGUAGAAGCUGGGGUGGUUUCCGCUAAAGCAGGAUAGAUGAUCAGUGUGGCCCCAGGGGCAGGGGAGGAGGGCUACUGGGACCUGGGUCUGUUCCUGCCUCAGAGGGAAGUUCUCCGUGAGCAUCAGUUUUCAAGCACACAGUCUUGAGGACAGCCUCUCUCUCCCUGGAGCCUGGCUCACGUUAUCUCUUGUGAAGCCCCCACACCCUCUUGCAGCCCUCUAAGUGGGACGUUUCCUUCAGAGACCACCCACAAGGGCUGCCCAAGUGGAACGGGCUGUGCGACAGAUGUGGGUCACUUCCGACUCUGGGACAAAAGCUGAGAAGAGAGGCCUCAGAGAAUAAAUAGGAGACUAAGAGGACAGGCAGACAAACAGGACGAGCCUGGGGGCUCCAGGCCUGGACGGAGGAAGAAGCCAGCUAUGCCAAUAAGAUAUGCAAAUGAUCUCCUUACCUUAUUGGUUGGAGGCCUCAGGACCACAGAUGACCUCAGAGAGCUGGCCCUUUAAGAAUGCCCUUUGGGCUCUGUGCCCACAGCCCCCUGGAGCUGAGCAGAGGCACCAGGCCCUGCUCCAUGGAGCCUUCAGUCUCCUGGGAAGCUGUGCCUGUCUGGCUCUGGCACUGACCACAUCCUCUCGGCCAUUUCUGAAGUGCACUCCUCCCAGCCCAGCUCCAGAAUGGCCCUGCCCCCCAGCCCCCUGGCCAUGGAAUAUGUCAAUGACUUUGACUUGAUGAAGUUUGAGGUAAAGCGGGAACCCUCUGAGGGCCGACCUGGCCCCCCUACAGCCUCACUGGGCUCCACACCUUACAGCUCAGUGCCUCCUUCACCCACCUUCAGUGAACCAGGCAUGGUGGGGGCAACCGAGGGCACCCGGCCAGGCCUGGAGGAGCUGUACUGGCUGGCUACCCUGCAGCAGCAGCUGGGGGCUGGGGAGGCAUUGGGGCUGAGUCCUGAAGAGGCCAUGGAGCUGCUGCAGGGUCAGGGCCCAGUCCCUGUUGAUGGGCCCCAUGGCUACUACCCAGGGAGCCCAGAGGAGACAGGAGCCCAGCACGUCCAGCUGGCAGAGCGGUUUUCCGACGCGGCGCUGGUCUCGAUGUCUGUGCGGGAGCUAAACCGGCAGCUGCGGGGCUGCGGGCGCGACGAGGCGCUGCGGCUGAAGCAGAGGCGCCGCACGCUGAAGAACCGCGGCUACGCGCAGGCCUGUCGCUCCAAGCGGCUGCAGCAGCGGCGCGGGCUGGAGGCCGAGCGCGCCCGCCUGGCCGCCCAGCUGGACGCGCUGCGGGCCGAGGUGGCCCGCCUGGCCCGGGAGCGCGAUCUCUACAAGGCUCGCUGUGACCGGCUAACCUCGAGCGGCCCCGGGUCCGGGGACCCCUCCCACCUCUUCCUCUGAGCCGUUCAGAGCACCUUGUGGUGUAGUGGGGGCUGGGUGGGGUGGCUCCGCCCAGGAGGCGGCUGCACGGUUCUCUGCAUCGUUACCAGAGCGCCUUCUGGUCCUAGCCACGCCCUGUAUGACCGCGCAAAUAUCCCCAAAGCUUUUGGGUCCUCAAGUCAUGCCCGAAUUUAGAUGCUGGUCAUUUUCUGGAGAGGGGUCCCCUCCCCUUACGAACACAGAAACCCAGCCCACAUGACUAGCACGCUGAGCUCUGCAGGGACCAGUGCCAGGCACUGGGGGGUGGAAGUGUGGUGACACAGUGAAUGGGAGGUGGAGGAGGGUUGCAGCUCCCACCUCAGUUUAGUUUUUAAUUCAGGGUUUUCAACCUGUAACACAUUAAAGCUGUAAUUAGCAAUGAGGCUGUAUUUUCAUUCUGAAGCUUGUAACCUCCCCAUUUUAGCACUACAGAAUUUUCAAGAUUUCAAUAUCCAACAACUAGAUAGAUUAGGACCUCUAUCCGAGAUGCUUUUUCCCUGCCCAACCCUGUGGCCUUCAGGGCUCAGAGCAGCAAAGGCCUGAAGAGUGAGCUCUGGGGGUUGUUGGUGUGGGUUGGGAGAGAGCUGUGUGCAGAAGUCUGGAAACCUGGGUCCUAGUCCCAGCUCUUCCAUGGGAUCCCCCUGUCACCCUGAGCAAAUCAGUUGCUUCCUGGACUUGUGUUACUUCAUCUAAUUCUCAUGUGGAUUGGACGACUUCUGCUCCCUUUCCAGUUCUGGCAUCUCCCCAGUAUGGAAGUCCCGGUGGUCUCCCCAAGAAGUCCCCAAGACAAUCUCGCCAAAGGCACCUCCUAUCCUGCUGCAGUUUCCCAGCUGCAGCCUAGGCAGGGGAUGCACAGCCCAGGCGAGGAAGCCUGGCUUCUCUGUGAGCACAUACGUGGGUCCUCGGCAGCUCCCUCCAGGCUGUCUGGGCCUCCAGACCUGCACAGGGUGCUCCUGCCACCUCCCACCUCUCUGAGGGCUGAGGUGAGACUUCUCCUGGGAUGACAAUUUGCUGAGAGAGUGCAGCUUUUGUGAAUUAAACUUGAAGUCCAGGCAGAAUUCUAAUGCAAUAAGCUAAAUGUUCUUGCAAUUUAAGAAGUGUUCAUUCUUUAUCCCUGCUUCAGGCUACUGUUUGUGUGUCUGUGUGUGGGAGAGGGAGAGAGAGGGAGAGAGAGAGAGAGCAAGAAAAAGGGAAGUCCCCACCUGGAGCUGGGUGGCACAUCUGUUAUGGAGAGCCAAUGGAAAUGGGGUGGAGGGGCAGGCAUUGGAACAGAUGGAUCCUCCCCCUCUCACCACCACCACCACCAAACUCAGAAGCCUCAGUGGCCCAGCUCGGCCUGUCAGUGGCUAUCCAGGUCUCACAGUUUCCAUGGUAACCCAGUCCUCCAGUUCAGCAGGCUAAGGGGAGGGCAGAUGGGGCCUCUGGGCAGAGCACAGGCGUUGUGCUGGGAGCAGCCGCCUCACGAGUUACUGUCAUCUGUCCUCUACCGGACAUAAUAAAUGGGAGAAGCUUUCGGGCAUGGGGGAAGAGGCUCCCAUAUGUCCCUCUUCCUUUCUACCCCCUCUCUCCACCCCCUCCCCAGCUGUCUCUUCUCUUCCCAUCACAGUUCUUGCUCCCUCUUUCCCCUCCUCUAUCCCAGCUCAUCCCUCCUCCGCUUAGGAGCCUGCAAUGGGAGUCCUCUCCUCCAUCGCUCUCAGAAUUUCUCUCGUCUCCUCUCCCUUCCCCACCAUUGGCCACUGGCCAUCCUCUCUGGCUCUGGAUUCUCUCUCUGAGGGGCUCACAGAACCUUUAGCUUCUCUUUCUUCAUCCCCUUCCACACUCAUUGUUGAAGGGAGAGGAUGGGGCAGGGAGGGUCCUUCCGGGAGCCCAGCUCUUUUUCUCUCACUCUAAAUUUCACCUGUGUCUAUCCUUGCCUGCCCUGGAGCUGUAAUUCAGACCCACUACUUUUCUUGUUCACUUUUCUCACCUGCAUGGCACACAAAGACAGACAGAACCAUCCAUAGACACCUGAGCACACAACUAGGCCACAUAUACAGUACCAUACCUGGGUCUCAAAAUGAUACUCCUGGGUUACCUGAGUAUACUUAAAAAAACAAAGUUGCACACUGUGGUGAUUAAGAGUAGUGCUUUAGGUGGGGCGCAGUGGUUCCUGCCUGUAAUCCCAACACUUUGGGAGGCCAAGGAGGAAGUUUGAGACCAGCCUGGGCAACAUAGCGAGAACCCUGUCACUACAAAAAAAUAAAAUAAAAUAAAUUCAGAUGUAAUGGCAUGCACCUGGAGUCCCACCUACCCAGGAGGCUAAGGUGGAAGGAUAACUUGAGCCCAGGAGUUCGGGGAUGCAGUGAGCCAUAAUCGUGCCACUGCAUUCCAGCCUGGGUGGCAGAGUGAGACCCUGUUUCAAGUUGCAGUUCUACCAGUUUUUUGACCAUGGGUGGGUUAAAAUCAAGCCUCACUUGAUUGUCAGAAAAAUGGUGAAAAUAAUGGUAACCACCUACUGAGAAUAAAUGCAUUUAAAUAAGCACUUAGCAUAAAGUUGACACAUGCUACGUAAUGAUA